AUUCCUGUCCGGACGCACCUGCAGCUCCCCGGGGAGAAGAGGACGCCCCCCAUCCGCUCCCCCACACAGGUGCCGGCGCGGGGCGGAGGCGUCUCGAGCUGUCACCUCGCCCCAGAGGCCAGACGUCUCCCGGCGGGGAUGCUGUGACGGCGGACGCUCUGGAGAAGGGGCUGGGGGUGGGGCUCUGCGAGCUCCGGGCGGACCCCGGCCUUGGAUUCCGGGGAGAAGGUUGCAUCCUGAGGCUGGGAAAGGAGAGGGUCUUUGGGGUCUCCUGACCGAUGCUUCUCCCCUCCAGGCUUGCGCCCCAGAGGACCCGCGCCCCAAGCCCCCGCGCCGCCCCCAGGCCCACCCGGAGCAUGCUGCCUGCAGCCAUGAAGGGCCUCGGCCUGGCGCUGCUGGCCGUCCUGCUGUGCUCGGCGCCCGCUCAUGGCCUGUGGUGCCAGGACUGCACCCUGACCACCAACUCCAGCCAUUGCACCCCAAAGCAGUGCCAGCCGUCCGACACGGUGUGUGCCAGUGUCCGAAUCACCGAUCCCAGCAGCAGCAGGAAGGAUCACUCGGUGAACAAGAUGUGUGCCUCCUCCUGUGACUUCGUUAAGCGACACUUUUUCUCAGACUAUCUGAUGGGGUUUAUUAACUCUGGGAUCUUAAAGGUCGACGUGGACUGCUGCGAGAAGGAUUUGUGCAAUGGGGCGGCAGGGGCAGGGCACAGCCCCUGGGCCCUGGCCGGGGGGCUCCUGCUCAGCCUGGGGCCUGCCCUCCUCUGGGCUGGGCCCUGAUGUCUCCUCCUUCCCACGGGGCUUCUGAGCUUGCUCCCCUGAGCCUGUGGCUGCCCUCUCCCCAGCCUGGCGUGGCUGGGGCUGGGGGCAGCCUUGGCCCAGCUCCGUGGCUGUGGCCUGUGGCUCUCACUCCUCCCCCGACGUGAAGCCUCCCUGUCUCUCCGCCAGCUCUGAGUCCCAGGCAGCUGGACAUCUCCAGGAAACCAGGCCAUCUGGGCAGGAGGCCUGGGGAUGAGGGUGGGGGGGGACCCCCAGGUCCCGGAGGGGAAGUGAAGCAACAGCCCAGCUGGAAGGGCGUCUUCUGCGGAGAAAUAAAGUCACUUUUGAGUCCUGA